GCUUUUCGCCCGCCGUUCCGUGGCGGGAACUGAGGCGACUGUGGGGACAUCAGUGAUCGUAAGUCUCCUGGGCCCGUUAUUCUCAGAUUAGGUGACGGAGCUAAGACUUCGAGACCAUCUCGUCCUUUUUGUAUCGCGGAAACCUGAGGAACGAGCCGGCGGCGGUGACCUGCACGAGAAGCCAGGCUAACUGGGUGAAGUACCAUGCAAGCAUUUCUUAAAGGUACAUCCAUCAGUACUAAACCCCCGCUGACCAAGGAUCGAGGAGUAGCUGCCAGUGCGGGAAGUAGCGGAGAGAACAAGAAAGCCAAACCCGUUCCCUGGGUGGAAAAAUAUCGCCCAAAAUGUGUGGAUGAAGUUGCUUUCCAGGAAGAAGUGGUUGCAGUGCUGAAAAAAUCUUUAGAAGGAGCAGAUCUUCCUAAUCUCUUGUUUUACGGACCACCUGGAACUGGAAAAACAUCCACUAUUUUGGCAGCAGCUAGAGAACUCUUUGGGCCUGAACUUUUCCGAUUAAGAGUUCUUGAGUUAAAUGCAUCUGAUGAACGUGGAAUACAAGUAGUUCGAGAGAAAGUGAAAAAUUUUGCUCAAUUAACUGUGUCAGGAAGUCGCUCAGAUGGGAAGCCGUGUCCGCCUUUUAAGAUUGUGAUUCUGGAUGAAGCAGAUUCUAUGACCUCAGCUGCUCAGGCAGCUUUAAGACGUACCAUGGAGAAGGAGUCGAAAACCACCCGAUUCUGUCUUAUCUGUAACUAUGUCAGUCGAAUAAUUGAACCCCUGACCUCUAGAUGUUCAAAAUUCCGCUUCAAGCCUCUGUCAGAUAAAAUUCAACAGCAGCGAUUACUAGACAUUGCCAAGAAGGAAAAUGUCAAAAUUAGUGAUGAGGGAAUAGCUUAUCUUGUUAAAGUGUCAGAAGGAGACUUAAGAAAAGCCAUUACAUUUCUUCAAAGCGCUACUCGAUUAACAGGUGGAAAGGAGAUCACAGAGAAAGUGAUUACAGACAUUGCCGGGGUAAUACCAGCUGAGAAAAUUGAUGGAGUAUUUGCUGCCUGUCAGAGUGGCUCUUUUGACAAACUAGAAGCUGUGGUCAAGGAUUUAAUAGAUGAGGGUCAUGCAGCAACUCAGCUCGUCAAUCAACUCCAUGAUGUGGUUGUAGAAAAUAACUUAUCUGAUAAACAGAAGUCUAUUAUCACAGAAAAACUUGCCGAAGUUGACAAAUGCCUAGCAGAUGGUGCUGAUGAACAUUUGCAACUCAUCAGCCUUUGUGCAACUGUGAUGCAGCAGUUAUCUCAGAAUUGUUAACGUGAAUAUAUCUGGAUGGGGGGUUUUGUAAAUAAUGAAGUUGUAAUAAAAAUAAAAUGACCAAAAGCA